AGGCCCGGAAACGCUCCCUGUCACAAAGGGGGGAACACGUGGGCGCCGGCUGCCGGGGCGGCGAUCUUAGGGAACUAGGGUCACCUGGAGAGCCGCCCACCGUCUCUGCCCGCUCGACUCCUCCGCCCGGGCCGCUCGGCCGGUCCAGCCGCGGCCGGCGCCUGGCUGUGAGGUGGAUUCCCGGCCCAGUCUGACCAUCUCCCUCCAGUUUUUCCACUUCGUUCGGACCUUCUCAUAACUAUGUCCACCCUCUACGUCUCCCCUCACCCAGAUGCCUUCCCCAGCCUCCGAGCCCUCAUAGCCGCUCGCUAUGGGGAGGCUGGGGAGGGUCCCGGAUGGGGAGGAGCCCACCCCCGCAUCUGUCUCCAGCCACCCCCGACUAGCAGGACUCCCUUUCCCCCACCCCGCCUGCCGGCCCUGGAGCAGGGGCCCGGUGGGCUCUGGGUGUGGGGGGCCACGGCUGUGGCCCAGCUGCUGUGGCCAGCAGGCCUGGGGGGCCCAGGGGGCAGCCGGGCGGCUGUCCUUGUCCAACAGUGGGUCAGUUACGCCGACACGGAGUUAAUACCAGCUGCCUGUGGAGCAACGCUGCCGGCCCUGGGACUCCGAAGCUCGGCCCAGGACCCCCAGGCUGUGCUGGGGGCCCUGGGCAGGGCCCUGAGCCCCUUGGAGGAGUGGCUUCGGCUGCACACCUACUUGGCCGGGGAGGCCCCCACUCUGGCUGACCUGGCGGCUGUCACAGCCUUGCUGCUGCCUUUCCGAUACGUCCUAGACCCACCUGCCCGCCGGAUCUGGAAUAAUGUGACUCGCUGGUUUGUCACGUGUGUCCGGCAGCCAGAAUUCCGAGCCGUGCUAGGAGAAGUGGUUCUAUACUCAGGAGCCAGGCCUCUCUCUCAUCAGCCAGGCCCCGAGGCUCCUGCCCUCCCAAAGACAGCUGCUCAGCUCAAGAAAGAGGCAAAGAAACGGGAGAAGCUAGAGAAAUUCCAACAGAAGCAGAAGAUCCAACAGCAGCAGCCACCUCCAGGGGAGAAGAAACCAAAACCAGAGAAGAGGGAGAAACGGGAUCCUGGGGUCAUUACCUAUGACCUCCCAACCCCACCCGGGGAAAAGAAAGAUGUCAGUGGCCCCAUGCCCGACUCCUACAGCCCUCGGUAUGUGGAGGCUGCCUGGUACCCUUGGUGGGAGCAGCAGGGCUUCUUCAAGCCAGAGUAUGGGCGUCCUAAUGUGUCAGCAGCAAAUCCCCGAGGUGUCUUCAUGAUGUGCAUCCCACCCCCCAAUGUGACAGGCUCCCUGCACCUGGGCCAUGCACUCACCAACGCCAUCCAGGACUCCCUGACUCGAUGG